GCAAUUACCAAAGGAGUCAAGACACCUUACAGCCCAGCCUUAAUUCAGAAACCCUCAUAAAGUAGAUGCAGAGGGCAGUAAGAUAUAACUCAACUUUGAAAAUGUCAGCCGUUAUAGUUGAAGAAAUCUGACCCAAGAGACUUCGCUCCGCUGCAAGAUGGAAGGAAGCUUAAGUAAGACAUAAAUUUGUAAUGAACUUGCUCACAACAUCCGCCGCCACUGUGACUUGCAGUCAUCAUCCAUUACCACAAAAUUAGUUGCAGGAUGGCUACUCGUAUCCCUCCACACAUGAUCAUCAGUAUUUGCCUCCUGUGUCCCAACCGGCCUGAGUCAAUAGAGAUGCGGUUUCACCAUGUUGGCCAGGAUGGUCUCGAUCUCUUGACCUCGUGAUCCGCCCGCCUCGGCCUCCCAAAGUGCUGGGAUUACAAGCGUGAGCCACUGCGCCUGGCCAGAAGACUGACGUUUUAUAAUUGAUGGUCACAACUUUAAAAAUUCAUACUCAGUUAUAGGUUUUUGUCUAAUAAAAACAUCACUGCUUAAUUUAUUUACAAAACAUGGAGUCCAUAGAGAGAAAAACAACAGGGGCCUCUUGAUAGUAAAAGGAUGAGAAACAGGGAAAACUUGUAAGUCAAUGGACACUUCCUUCAGAAACUACAUUCAAAACUUAAAAAUUUUGUUAAAGAGUAAGCAACUGCCAAAUUCUCCUAAGUGACUUCAACGUGUUACUUAUACAUCAGAUAUGUACAUACAUAUUCCUAUAAUCAAGUAAUUCUAAGUUUGGGAAAAUAUCAUAAAUAAUAAUAGUUAUCUUUUGAAAAUAAAGUGGGGCUCUAGAUCAACCAGUGUCAGGAAGCAGCCAAGUCACACCCCACUGGGUGCUUCCUGGACAAGCGCAGUGCAGCUCCCACAGGGCCUCACACCCAACCUUCAAUUUGCUUAAAAGAACUAUCUCAAAAAAUCUUAGCUAUUUAGUCACAAUUUGUCCUUGCCAGGGAACAUGUUUUUCUUUUGCCUGAUUUUCAAUAACCUUAGAUUGCAAAAUCAUAAAAGCACUCAUCAAAGAACUGUGAGAGCAGCUCAGCUUCCCUGGAGAUCUCAAACCAUGUUCCUUUGAUACAAUGCAAUCAGCUCUUUAUACUUUAGGAACCUAAUUUUCCCUUACUAAAUGCUAAACAAUUUACAAAUAACACAAUGGCUACAGAAAAAAAAAAUCCAACAUCUUUACAUUCAAAUCCCAAAGAUAUAAACCUGACGUCUAAAUUAAUACGUGCUUAGUGCAAAACUGGGCAAUUAUUCCACAUUUGCAAGACAGUAUAACAUGACCACCUGCUGCUGAAAUGCCAAAGCCACCACUGUUAACGCUUUGCUCCGCCUUCCAGAGAGGUUAUUACAGCUUAAGCUGCGUCAACAACCCAGAGGAGGCUGCUAUCUAGUUUAUCUGUGUGGAAGGCCUGUAACACACUGUUAACAGAGUAGUUGCAGGCCCUUCCUUGGGAUAUUUUUCUGCGUAUAAGAGUGAAUGAACUCCACGGCCAGAUCCUCCUAGUCAUGUUGCAGUGCUGGUCAUGGGACCGCAGAGGGAACAGCACCCAACUGGGGAUGGGGAGCUCACAGGCACAGGCCCCGCAGCUGAUGCAAACCUUCCCCCUCCAAGGUUCUCUCGAGUCUCUGCCAAGAGUCGGCUGGAGGGCCCAACUGCUAUGUUCUUAUUGCUGUAAUGACUGCAAUUUGGCAGCAUCCAGGAUGGUGUACCGGGAACGGGAGGGGGAAGGAGAUGGUGGGCCCCUCUGUUAAACGCAACGCCAGAAGGGACACAGGAUGAAUUUAUUGUGGCCAUCGGUCCUGAGCUGGAAGGAAAGUCAAAGGGCUUUAAAGCUGGGGAAAAGCUCUAACUCCUGCUCUGCUGUCAAAGCCUUACUUCCCACGAAGAGUAGGGGCCAGGCGGGCCAACUGUAAGGGGGAAGCGGCCCGGGGUGAGGGUUACGACUCACUGAUUAAAAAGAGGGACUUUUUCAAAUACUUUGCACUUUUGAUUGUGUAUUAUGGAUACCAAGGAAGAGAAGAAGGAACGGAAACAAAGUUAUUUUGCUCGACUGAAAAAGAAAAAACAAGCCAAACAAAAUGCAGAGACAGCCUCAGCUGUAGCUACAAGGACUCAUACUGGGAAGGAAGAUAAUAAUACAGUAGUUUUAGAGCCAGACAAGUGCAACAUUGCUGUGGAAGAGGAAUAUAUGACUGAUGAGAAAAAAAAGAGAAAAAGUAAUCAGUUAAAGGAGAUCAGGCGUACAGAACUAAAGAGAUAUUAUAGUAUUGAUGACAAUCAAAACAAAACACAUGAUAAAAAAGAGAAGAAGAUGGUGGUUCAGAAGCCCCAUGGGACUAUGGAAUACACUGCUGGAAACCAGGACACCCUAAACUCCAUAGCACUGAAAUUUAACAUCACUCCCAAUAAAUUGGUGGAACUGAAUAAACUUUUCACACAUACUAUUGUUCCAGGCCAGGUCCUUUUUGUGCCAGAUGCCAACUCUCCUUCCAGUACCUUAAGGCUAUCAUCAUCCAGUCCUGGUGCUACUGUCUCUCCUUCAUCAUCAGAUGCAGAAUAUGAUAAAUUGCCUGAUGCUGACUUAGCACGAAAGGCCUUGAAACCCAUUGAAAGAGUCUUAUCGUCUACUUCUGAAGAAGAUGAGCCAGGUGUGGUGAAAUUUUUAAAAAUGAAUUGUCGAUACUUCACCGAUGGAAAGGGUGUGGUUGGCGGUGUUAUGAUAGUGACUCCUAACAACAUCAUGUUUGACCCUCAUAAAUCUGAUCCUCUGGUUAUUGAAAAUGGGUGUGAGGAGUAUGGUCUCAUCUGCCCCAUGGAAGAGGUUGUUUCCAUUGCGCUCUACAAUGACAUUUCUCACAUGAAGAUCAAAGAUGCCUUGCCAUCUGACCUACCUCAGGAUCUUUGUCCUCUGUACAGGCCUGGAGAAUGGGAAGACCUGGCUUCAGAAAAGGAUAUCAACCCAUUCAGUAAGUUCAAAUCUAUCAACAAGGAAAAACGACAGCAGAAUGGAGAGAAAAUUAUGACUUCGGAUUCCAGACCAAUAGUACCUUUGGAGAAGUCCACAGGACAUACACCUACAAAGCCCUCAGGCAGCUCUGUGUCAGAGAAAUUAAAGAAACUGGACUCCUCUAGGGAGACAUCCCAUGGUUCUCCCACAGUGACUAAGCUCAGCAAGGAACCUUCCGACACUUCUUCUGCAUUUGAAUCUACAGCCAAAGAAAACUUUCUAGGGGAAGAUGAUGAUUUUGUUGACUUGGAAGAACUUUCUUCUCAAACUGGUGGUGGAAUGCACAAAAAAGACACCUUGAAGGAGUGCCUUUCUCUUGACCCAGAGGAACGAAAGAAAGCUGAGUCACAAAUAAACAAUUCUGCCGUGGAAAUGCAGGUGCAGUCAGCCCUAGCCUUUUUGGGAACAGAGAAUGAUGUUGAACUGAAGGGGGCGCUAGAUUUAGAAACCUGUGAGAAGCAAGAUAUAAUGCCAGAAGUGGACAAGCAGUCUGGUUCGCCAGAAAGCCGAGUAGAAAACACACUGAACAUACAUGAAGAUUUAGAUAAAGUUAAACUCAUUGAAUAUUACCUGACUAAGAACAAAGAAGGGCCACAGGUAUCUGAAAAUUUGCAGAAAACAGAAUUAAGUGAUGGAAAAAGUAUUGAACCAGGGGGAAUAGACAUUACCCUUAGUAGUUCUCUUUCCCAGGCGGGUGAUCCCAUAACUGAGGGCAAUAAAGAGCCAGAUAAGACCUGGGUGAAAAAGGGAGAGCCCCUCCCGGUAAAACUGAACUCUUCUACAGAAGCAAAUGUGAUUAAAGAGGCUCUAGACUCCUCUUUGGAAUCUACUCUGGACAACAGCUGUCAAGGUGCACAAAUGGAUAAUAAAUCUGAAGUUCAGUUGUGGCUGUUAAAGAGAAUUCAGGUACCCAUUGAAGAUAUACUUCCUUCAAAAGAAGAAAAAAGCAAGACCCCACCCAUGUUCCUGUGCAUCAAAGUGGGAAAACCAAUGAGAAAAUCCUUUGCCACUCACACUGCAGCCAUGGUCCAGCAGUACGGCAAACGGAGAAAGCAGCCAGAGUACUGGUUUGCUGUUCCUCGGGAGAGGGUGGAUCAUUUGUACACAUUCUUUGUUCAGUGGUCUCCCGAUGUCUAUGGAAAAGAUGCCAAAGAGCAAGGCUUUGUGGUGGUGGAGAAGGAAGAACUGAACAUGAUUGACAACUUCUUCAGUGAGCCAACAACCAAGAGCUGGGAGAUCAUCACUGUUGAAGAGGCAAAGCGCAGGAAGAGCACAUGCAGCUACUAUGAAGACGAGGACGAAGAGGUGCUGCCUGUCCUACGGCCCCACAGCGCGCUCCUGGAGAAUAUGCACAUCGAGCAGCUGGCCCGACGCCUUCCUGCAAGGGUGCAAGGGUAUCCAUGGAGACUGGCCUAUAGCACGUUAGAGCACGGGACCAGCUUAAAGACGCUCUACCGGAAAUCGGCAUCACUAGACAGUCCUGUCCUAUUGGUCAUCAAAGAUAUGGAUAAUCAGAUUUUUGGAGCAUAUGCAACUCAUCCUUUCAAGUUCAGUGACCACUAUUAUGGCACAGGCGAAACUUUUCUCUACACAUUCAGCCCUCAUUUUAAGGUCUUUAAGUGGAGUGGAGAAAAUUCAUACUUUAUCAAUGGAGACAUAAGUUCUUUAGAACUUGGUGGUGGAGGGGGACGAUUUGGUUUAUGGCUAGAUGCUGAUUUAUACCACGGACGAAGCAACUCUUGCAGCACUUUCAAUAAUGAUAUUCUUUCCAAAAAGGAAGACUUCAUAGUUCAGGAUCUGGAGGUGUGGGCAUUUGAUUGAAAUUCAGACUGCCUUAAAAUAUAACAUUAAAAAGACUGGGUUCGAUCAGCCCUCCUAAAGCUGGCUGGAAAAAGAAGCCCCAGCCCAGCCUGCCUCAUCCCACCCCAAUGCUUCCUUUCUGCCAUCAUCUCAGAGCAUGAUCACAUUGCAGAAAGAUUCUGGAAGGUCCAUGUAGAGGGCAGACAUUGAAGAAAGAAACUUAAAAUCCAGGUUGUUGAAAAGACUUUGUACUCCCACUUCCUCCAAAUCCAUACAGUGAGGAAUCAGAGUGUUUAUAGAUAUAUGAGUUGAAUGCAAUUUUUAUUUUUGGUAACUGUGAAAAAUAAGAUACUGUGGAUAUAUACAUGCCUUGUGUAUUUAUCAGCAUAAUUUUCAUUACCAAAAUGUACAGCUAUUAUUUGCCAUGGAAAAGGUUAGUCUCAUUUAGAAAAAUCGAAAGUGCACAGCACUUAAAGGGAAUAUAUGAGGUUUUUUUUUUUUUAAAAAAAAACUUUUAUUUAUUAUUUGUAGUAUAUUGUCUGAAAUGUGUCGGCAGUUUUUUUUCUUUUAAUGUGUCAAAUCUUGAAAUAUUAAAUGUAUACAUUUUGUGCUAUGUUUUGGGAACAAAUCUGUUUGAUUUAUAUAGUUUUAUAUUGAAUUUUUUUUGCCCUGAUUGUUUAGGGUGAUAGGUCUUAAGCAGCAUAUAUCUAUAUAUCUGUAUGUGGGUAUAUAGAGAUAUAUGUGUGUGUGUAUGUAUAUGUACAUAUACAUAUAUAUGAGUGUAUAAUUCUAAAUUUCUAAAAACUCAUUAUGAAUGUUCAUCAAUUUGACUAUUAUAGGCCAGCUUUCCAUUUAGUCAAUAAAAGCGUACAUUUUUAGUUACUUACCUUGAACAUAUUCGUGUGAAAAAGAAUACAUCAUUUCUCACAGUCUUAAGUUGAUAUUUAUAGAAAUGAAUACCUUUGUGAACCUAGACUUAGAACAAAUCCUGCUUUUGAAAAAAAAUGUUUUGCUUCUUACAAAAUCAUUUGUGUUAAUAACAAAAACUUUAUUUUCGGAGUGUUCUUUGUAUAACUUUUCCAAGCUUUUACAUUAACGAGCAGGCCUCUGUCUUAAAAGGGACUCAGUAUAUUAAUUUCUGCAUUUUUUAAAUCAAAUGAAAAACGUCAAAUUGGACCAAUUGUCUUGGUUUCUUGAUUCAUUUAUUUGAGAAAAAAACAAUACAAAGAAAUGCAUUCAUAUCAAAAUUGGAAUAGAAAGGAAAACCUAUUUUUAAGAUAUCAACCUAUUUUCACAUCAUAAAACAUCUAUUACAUAAAAUAAAGGUCCAGGCAUAGUGGCUCUUGCCUGUAAUCCCAGCACUUUGGGAGGCCGAGGCAGGUGGAUCACUCAAGGUCACAAGUUUGAGACCAGUCUGGCCAACAUGGUGAAACCCCAUCUCUACUAAAAGUACAAAUAUUAGCCGACUAUGUGGCGGGCACCUGUAAUCCCACCUACUCGGGAGGCUGAGGCAGGAGAAUUGCUUGAAUCCGGGAAGCAGAGGUUGUAGUGAGCCAAGAUCGUGCCACUGCACUCUAUCCUGGGUAACAGCGAGACUCUGUCUUAAAAAUAAUAACAAUAAUAAUAAUAAUAAAGACUUACUUAACCAAUAUUAUUGAUUACCAGACUUUUAUGAAAGCCAAAGACUGCUUGCUAGUAGGAAAAAAUUUCAAAUAAUAACCAAAGCUGAAAAAUGGUCUGUCAUAAAUUAUUUCCCCGGUAAUUUUUGAAAGGAAAAAUGUAUAACAAGUACUAUUUACAUAUCUGCAUUUAAAAAAGCAAUUCUUAGAAUACUUCCUUUACAUUAUUCUCCUAUUUUAGACAUUUUGUGAAAGAGAACAAAUUGUCCAGUGGCCUCCUGUCAGAUCAACAAUUAUUAUACUCCUUAAUUCCAUGCAAAUUUAAAUGAAUGCUAUAAAAUUUUAAAUCUGUAGCCUGGGUGUACGUUUCACUCAAGUUCUCCUACUGAGGACUCUUGACUAACAGCAUACUGGCAGUUUCACCUUAACCUGCUCGUUAAAUAAUGUGUUGGUGUGAGAUAUCAGGAAUGUCUCAUGAUAUCACGUUUACCAUUUACACCAUCUGCAACCAUAUGCUAUUAAUAAAAUGGAAAAAAACAAAAUGGUCAUUUUGCAUAUACUUCACUCUGACCUAGUUUAGUCCAUGAUACUAUAAUUGUGAGAGCAUAUCCAGAUGCUGUGUUCUCUAUGUAAAACAGUAUUGUCCAUUCAGAAAUGUGUGACCCUUCAUUUAUGGAUAUUGACUAUAUGUAAUGCAGUGCUAUCCCAAUAUUUUCAAUAAAGGACUUUAUGCAUUCAGUGAUUUUCUUUCCCAAAGAUUCAUUCAUCAGGUAUUUACUGGGUACCAGAGUGUUUAUUUUUGUGAGAGGAUGGUGAAAUAUCCAAGACUAAACAAGGUCCAGAGCUCAUGUUUUCACUGCUGCCCUGGAAACUCCCUCUUCAUUCCCUGUAGCCACCCUCCUAAUUGUCUCAUCAGUUCACGGAAACUGCUCUCAUUAUGGUUACCAGAGACAACUCUUGGCUGUAUCUACCAGUCUCUUCUAAUCUUUCUAGCUGUGCAAUGAAUGACAACCUCCUCCUCUUAACAUCUGUCUUAACCUACUUCAUAAUUUCCGUAAGGGACACUUUACUCUCUGAUAAAUUUUCUUUGGCAUCCUGACACCUAGCCCCUAGAUGUUGGGCUAGAUGAAGACCCCAAGCAGUCUUCAUUGCUUCAUAAUUCCUCAGUUCAUAAGUCCAUAUCAAAGGACUUGGGUGGGAGGAGGCAACCAAAUGUUUCUUCAGACUCUACUGAAAAUGAUUAGAUGCAUCCCCGUGCUACAAGCCACCAGAGACAUCCUGCACUAUUAUAAGUAUGUCUUCCCUUAAUUUGAUCUCCCUCUCCUUGAUGCCUUUUAAAGUUUUAGAGACACAUUGAUAUGGUUUGGCUGUGUGUCCCCACCAACAUCUCAUUGGAAUUAUAAUCCCCACAUGUUGAGGGAGGGACCUAGUGGGAUGUGAUUAGAACAUGGGGGCGGUUUCCCCCAUGCUGUUCUCAUGAUAGUGAGGGAGUUUUCAUGAGAUCUGUUUUAAAAUGUUUGGCAGUUCCACCCUCACCCUCUCUUCUGCUGCCAUGUAAGAUGUGCCUUGCUUCCCCUUUGCCUUCUGCCAUGAUUGUAAAUUUCCUGACGCCUACCCAGCCAUGUGAAACUGUGAGUCCAUUAAACCUCUUUUCUUUAUAAAUAA